AGUGCAUGUAUCCUUUUGAUAUACUGAUUUUCUGUCCUUUGAAUAAAUACCCAGUAGUGAUAUUGCUGGAUCUUACGGUAGUUCUGUGUUUAAUUUUUUGAAAAAUCUCCAUACUAUUUUCCAUAAUGGCUGUACUAAGUUACAUUCCCACCUACAGUGUAUGAGAGCUCCUUUUACUCUGCAUCCUUGCCAGCAUCUGUUAGUUUUUGUCUUUUUGAUAAUAGCUAUUCUAACUGGGUAAGAUGAUAUCAUUGUGGUUUGGAUUUGCAUUUCCCUGAUAAUUAGUGAUGUUGGGCAUUUUUUUAUAUACCUGUUGGCUACUCAUAUGUAUUUUGAGAAAUCUCUAUUGCCCACUUUUUUCCCCUUUUAUUGAUAUAUAAUUUACAUAUUUAUGGUGUACAUGUGAGUGUUUGUUACAUGCAAAGAAUAUGUAAUGAUCAAGUCAGGGUGAUUGGGGUAUCCAUCACCUAGAAUGUUUUAUCAUUUUUAUAUGUUGGUAUCAUUUCAAGCCCUCUCUUCUAAUUACUUUGAAAUGUACAUAUUAUUAUUGCUAAGUAUGGUCACCUUAGUCUGCUAUCAAACAUUGGAACUUAUUUCUUCUAUCUAACUGUAUGUUUGGGUACAUAAGAAAUAAGUUCCAGUGUUGGAUAGCAGACUAGGGUGACUAUACUUCUUAUAGUCUUUGUCUCUCUCCCCUCUUUAUCCCCUCUCCUCCUCCCCUUCCCAGUCUCUGUUAUCUAUUGUUCUAUACUCUAUGUCCAUGAGAUCAAGUUUUUUAGCUCCCACAUAUGAGUGAGGACAUGCAAUAUUUGUCUUUCUAUGCCUGGCCUAUUUCACUUAAAAUAAUGAUCUCCAUUUCUAUCCAUGUUGCUGCAAAUGACAUUAUUUCAUUAUGGCCAAAUAGUAUUCUAUUGUUUAACACACUUUAUCCGUUUAUCUGUUGCUGGGCAUUUAGGUUGAUUCCAUAUCUUUGCUAUUGUGAAUAAUACUGUGGUGAACAUAUGAGAGUGUCCUUUUGAUACACUGAUUUCUUCUUUGGAUAGAUACCCAAUAGUGAGAUUGCUGGGUCUUAAUGGUAGUUCUAAUUUUACUUUUUGAGAAAUCUCCAUACUGGUUUAUUUACUAAUUUACAUUCCCACCAGCAGUGUAUAAGAGUUCCCUUUUCUUACCAGCAUCUGUUAUUUCCUGUCUUUUUAAUAAUAGAGGUUCCAGCUGGGGUAAGAUAUCUUAUUAUGGUUUGGAUUUGCAUUUCACUGAUGAUUAGUGAUUAGCAUUUUUUCAUAUACCUGUUGGCCAUUUGUAUGUCUUUUGAGAAAUGUCUAUUUCAUGUCCUUCACCCACUUUUUAAUGGCAUUUUUUUUUUUUUUUGCUAUUGAGUUGUUUUGAGUUCCUUCUAUAUUCUGGAUAUUAGUCACUUGUCAGAUGAAUAUUUUGUAAACGUUUUCUCUCAUUCAUCAGGUUGUCUCUUCUGCUGAGGGUUUUCUUUGCUGUACGGAAGUGUUUUAGUUUAAUACAGUCCCAUUUAUCUAUCUUUGUUUUUGUUUCCUGUGCUUUUGGGAUCUUGGCCAUAAACUCUUUGCCUCAACCAGUGUCCCUGGAGCAUUUCUCCUGUGUUUUCUUCUAGUAGUUUUAUAGUUUGGGGCCUUAUCUUAAGUCUGUAAUCCAUUUUGUUUUGAUUUUUUAUAUGGUGAGAGACAGGGGUUUAGUUUUAUUCUUCUCCAUGUGGAUAUUUAGUUCUCCUAGCACCAUUUAUUGAAGAGGGUAUUCUUUCCCCAGUAUACGUUCUUGACACCUUUGUUGAAAAUCAGUUGGAUAUAAAUAUGUGGAUUUAUUUCUGGAUUCUCUAUUCUGUUCCAUUUUGGUCUAUGUGUCUGUUUUUAUACUAAUACUAUGCUAGUUUGGUUAUGAUAGCCUUGUGGUAUAUUUUGAAGUCAGGUAGUGUGAUGCCUCUAGCUGUUCUUUUUGCUCAGGUUUGCUUUGGUUAUUCAGGCUCUUUGUAGUUUCAUGCAAAUUUUAGAAUUGUUUGUUCUAGUUCUGUGAAAAAUAUUAUUGGUAUUUUGGUAGAGAUUGCGUUGAAUCUGUAGAUUGCUUUUGGUAGAAUGGUCAUUUUCACCAUAUUAAUUCUUCCGAUCCAUGAACAUGGGAUGUCUUUCCAUUUUUUUGUGUCCUCUUUAAUUUCUUUCAUCAAUGUUUUAUAGUUUUCCUUGUAGAGGUCUUUCACCUUGGUAAAAUUUAUUCCUAGGGUUUUGGGUUUUGUUUUUAGUUUUGGAAAUAUGAUUGCUUUCUUGAUUUCUUUUUCCUCUAGUUUGUUGCUAGUAUAUUGAAAGUUAUACUGAUUUUUCAUGUUGAUUUUGUGUCUUGCAGCUUUACUGAAUUUGUUCAUUAGUUUUAAGAGGUUUUUUUUGUGUGUGUGUGUAGUCGUUUGGUUUUUCUAAAUAUAAGAUCAUGUCAUCUGCAGAGAGGGACAGUUUGACUUCCUCUUUUCCAGUUUGGAUGCUUUUAAUUUCCUUCUCUUACCUGAUUGCUUUGGCCAGGACUUCCAGUAUUGUGUUGAAUAAGAGUGGUGAAAGUGGGCAUCCUUGUCUAGUUCCAGUUCUUAGAGGAAAAGCUUUCAGCUUUUCUCUGUUCAGUAUGUUAGCUAUGGGUUUGUCAUAUAUGGCCUUUAUUAUGUUGAGGUAUAUUCUUUCUUUUUAUUUUUAUUUAUUUGUUUAUUUAUUUUUUGAGAUGAAGUCUCACUCUGUUGCCCAGGCUGGAAUGCAGUGGCACGACCUCAACUCUUUGCAACCUCUGCCUGCUGGGUUCAAGUGACUCUCCUGCCUCAGCCUCCCAAGUAGCUGGGACUACAGGCAUGCACCACCAUGUCUGGCUAAUGUUUUUUGUAUUUUUAGUAGAGAUGGCGUUUCACCAUGUUGGCCAGGCUGGUCUCAGACUCCUGACCUCAAGUGAUCUGCUCGCCUUGGCCUCCCAAAGUGCUGGGAUUAUAUGUGUAAGCCAUCGUGCCCGGCCAAGGUAUGUUUUUUCUGUGCCUAGUUUGUUGAACAUUUUUAUCAUGAAGGGAUGUUGAGUUUUAUUGAAUGCUUUUUCUGCCCCAAUUGAGAUGAUCAUAUGGUUUUUGUCUUUUAUUAUGUUGAUGUGAUAUAUCAUAUUUAUUGAUUUGCAUAUGGUAAAUUAUCUUUACAACUCAGGGAUAAAUCCCACUUGAUUGUGGUAUAUUGUCCUUUUGAUGUACUGUUGGAUUUGGUUUGGUAGUAUUUUGUUGAAGACUUUUGCAUCUGUGUUCAACUAUGGCCUGUAGUUUUUUUGUUUUGUUUUGUUUUGUUUUUUAAUGUUGUGCCUUUGUCUGGUUUUGGUUUCAGGGCUUCACAGAAUGAGUUAGGAAGAAUUCCCUUCUCUUUUAUUUUUUGGAAUAGUUUGAGGAGAAUUGGUAUUCUUUGUAAGUUUGGUAGACUUUGGCAGUGAAGCCAUCAGAUUCUGAGCUUUUCUUUUUUAGGAGACUUUUUAUUACUGAUUCAAUCUCAUUACUCGUUGUUUGUUCAGGUUUUCUGUUUCUUCCUGAUUCAAUCUUGGUAGGUUUUAUGUGUCCAAGAAUUUGUCCAUGUCCUUUAGGUUUUCCAGUUUGUUGGUGUAUAGUUGUUUGUAGUAGUAUCUGAUGAUCUUUUGUAUUUCUGUAGUGUCAGUUGUAAUGUCUCCUUUUUCAUUUCUGCUUUUGUUUGAGUUCUUGGUUGGUCUAGAAACAUAAUUUUGUAAAAUGGUUUUCUUGUUAAACACUUGAACCAUCAUUCUUGAUCAUCUGGUGUGUAGAAGACACUGUACUGGAUACUACUGGUAGUAAGUAGAAGGCUGCAUAAGACAGAUCUGUGCUCUCAAGGAGAUUUGUUAUACAUUAUGAAAAUGAAUUUAUAGGUAAUUCAAGUUAAAACUAAAAUAUCUUCACUUCUGAGAGAAGCUAAAAUUUCAGAAGCUGCUAAGGGGCUUUGUUAGGAUUAGGGGCUUUUCUCAUUGCGUAACCAGGAAUAAAAGACAGCCUUACUUUGAGAAGACCAUAAACGGGUGAAUGGAUAAACAAUUUGUGCCAUGUUUAUACAAUGGAAACACUACUUGGCAAGAAAGAACAGACUUGAUACAUGAUGUGAAUUAAUCUCAAACUAAUUAUGCUGAAAGAAGUAGAUAACCCCCCCAUACAAAGUAUAUAUGUUUCUGGGUUUUGGCUAUUACAACUAAACUGGCUAUAAACAUUUGUAUACAAUUCUUUAUGUGUACAUAGGCUUUCAUUUCUCUUAGGUAAAUACCUGUGCAUGGAAUGGCUGGGUCGCUUAGGGUAUCUGUUUAAAUAGUCAUUUUUCUAAUUAUUGUAAAUGUCACUUCUUUCUUAUACUAGGUUUCUAUAUAUGCUUGUGUUCAUUUUUGUCUCUUGUCUGUGGAUCUGCUUUGCACUGUAUUAGCACUAUUAUAUAUACUGUUUUAAUUUAUGUGGCUUUAUAAUAUAUCUAAUGCAUAUUUUGGGAAAAUUUUUACCCUGUUGCUUUCCUAUGGAAUUGUUUCAUAUAAACACAUUUUUAGUUUAUUUGCAUAUUCUUCAAAACCUAAAUAUUUGAAUAUUAAAGAAAAAUGUGGAAAACAGAAAAUUUUCCUUUUAUGAUGAGAUACAGUAUUGUAAGACAGUUAGAUUAUGAGAAUCUUGUCCUGUGUAUGGGAUUUGAGUCAUCAGUGCUGAACUGUUGAAAUAAGACUUGUCAAAAAUGAUACAUUCAGAUCCUUUUGGAUAGGAAGUAUAAUUUUUCUUUUGUUCAUAUUUAGAACCAUUCUGAAAACACAGCCAUGGAUGAAAUGAUCUCUCUGUAACAUUUUCUCUGUCACAUUUUUAUGUUGUAAGAGUAUGUCUUUGCUUGCCAGUAUACCUUGCCAGGGUUGAGUAAUACCAUUUUUAAAAUAUUUACCAACAUGAUAGAUGAUAAAAGUUAAUAUUUUUAUUUUCACCUCUUUAGUUAUUGCUAAGAUUGAACAUUUUUAAUAUAGUUAAGAGUCAUGUAUAUUUUCUCUUUUCUAAAUUUUCUCUUCAUAGCCAUGUCUUUUUUUUUUUUUUUGAGAUGGAGUCUUGCUCUGUCACCCAGGCUGGAGUGCAGUGGCGCAGUCUCAGCUCACUACAACCUCCUCCAUCUCCCAGGUUCAGGUGAUUCUCCUGCCUCAGCCUCCCAAGUAGCUGGGACUACAGGCGCGUGCCACCAUGCCCGGCUAAUUUUUUAUUUUUUUACUUUUAGUAGAGAUGGGGUUUCGCUGUUUUAGCCAGGAUUGUCUUGAUCUCCCAACCUCAUGAUCCACCCGCCUUGGCCUCCCAAAGUGCUGGGAUUACAGGCGUGAGCCACUGCGCCCAGCCAGCCAUGUCUAUUUUUUUCUGUUGUAGUUAGUGUUUGUCUUAGGUCUGAGCUUAUAUUACAUAAUGAAAAUGUUAGGGUACUCAUCACAGCCCUUAAACUUUGUACUUACAAGAGUUGUGAGAAUGUGGACAAAUAGAGAUUGCUGAGUUGUAAGACUUUUAAUAAAUGAUCUGUUGCUAAGUUUAAAAAAGUAAAAAAGAACAGGAAGUUCUCAGCACGACAGAAAAUUUUAGCUGUGAGCCAUUUGAAAGAAGGAUUGGUUCUUGAACUGUUUUUGUUUAGCUAAGAGCCAUUUUGGAUAAUUGGGUAGGUGCAACUUUUAUUUAAGAAAGAAGCUCAUAUGUCCCAUUGUGCUUUAUUAGUUAUGGAAUAAUUAUUUCUACAAAAAGAAAAAAUUCAGAACCCUUUACUAAAUUUUUGUGUUAAAAUAAAUUUAUUAUUGAAGGAAGGUAAUUUAAUAAUAUAAAUAAUGGUCUAGUACCUAUACUUUUUUCAAUGUCAUUAGACUAUAUUUUGUUUCCUGGUGAAGGAGUACCAAUAAUACAGACCUAAUUCCCUUUUUUUUUUGAAAUGGAGUCUCACUUUGUCAUCCAGACUGGAGUGUAGUGGCACGAUCUCAGCUCACUGCAACCUCCGCCUCCCGGGUUCAAGUGAUUCUCCUGCCUCAGCCUCCUGAGUAGCUGGGAUUACAGGCACGUGCCACCAUGCCUGGCUAAUUUUUUUUUUGUAUUUUUAGUAGAGACGGGGCUUCAUCAGGUUGGCCACGCUGAUCUCAAACUCCUGAGCUCAAGUGAUCCAGCCGCCUCAGCCUCCCAAAGCGCUGGGAUUACAGACCUCUGUGAGUGAAAGCCUUCAGAGGGAAGCUGCUAAGAAGCAGGCCAUGAAACAGACCAAACUGGAAAUCCAGAAGGCCCUUGCAGAAGAUGCUACUGUGUAUGAAUAUGACAGUAUUUAUGAUGAAAUGCAGAAAAAAAAGGAGGAAAAUAAUCCCAAAUUGCUUUUGGGGAAAGACAGAAAGCCCAAGUAUAUUCACAACUUGCUAAAAGCAGUUGAGAUCAGAAAAAAGGAACAGGAAAAAAGAAUGGAAAAGAAAAUACAGAGAGAACGAGAAAUGGAAAAGGGGGAGUUUGAUGAUAAAGAAGCAUUUGUGACAUCUGCAUAUAAGAAAAAACUGCAAGAGAGAGCUGAAGAAGAAGAAAGAGAAAAGAGGGCUGCUGCACUGGAAGCAUGUUUGGAUGUAACCAAGCAGAAAGAUCUCAGUGGAUUUUAUAGGCACCUAUUAAAUCAAGCAGUUGGUGAAGAGGAAGUACCUAAAUGCAGCUUUCGUGAAGCCAGAUCUGGUAUAAAGGAAGAAAAAUCAAGGGGCUUCUCCAAUGAAGUAAGUUCAAAAAACAGAAUACCACAAGAGAAAUGCAUUCUUCAAACUGAUGUGAAAGUAGAGGAAAACCCAGAUGCAGACAGUGACUUCGAUGCUAAGAGCAGUGCGGAUGAUGAAAUAGAAGAAACUAGAGUGAACUGCAGAAGGGAAAAGGUCAUAGAGACCCCUGAGAAUGACUUCAAGCACCACAGGAGUCAAAACCACUCUCGGUCACCUAGUGAAGAAAGAGGGCACAGUACCAGGCACCACACGAAAGGAUCACGAACGUCGAGAGGACAUGAGAAAAGGGAAGAUCAGCACCAGCAGAAGCAAUCCAGAGACCAAGAGAACCAUUACACUGACCGUGAUUACCGGAAAGAAAGGGAUUCUCAUAGGCACAGAGAGGCCAGUCAUAGAGAUUCCCAUUGGAAGAGGCAUGAACAGGAAGAUAAACCAAGGGCGAGGGACCAAAGAGAAAGAAGUGACAGAGUAUGGAAAAGGGAGAAAGAUAGGGAGAAAUAUUCCCAAAGAGAACAAGAAAGAGAUAGACAACAAAAUGAUCAGAACCGACCCAGUGAGAAAGGAGAGAAGGAAGAGAAAAGCAAAGCAAAGGAAGAGCAUAUGAAAGUAAGGAAGGAAAGAUAUGAAAAUAAUGAUAAAUACAGAGAUAGAGAAAAACGAGAGGUAGGUGUUCAGUCUUCAGAAAGAAAUCAAGACAGAAAGGAAAGCAGCCCAAAUUCUAGGGCAAAGGAUAAAUUUCUUGACCAAGAAAGAUCCAACAAAAUGAGAAACAUGGCAAAGGACAAAGAAAGAAACCAAGAGAAACCCUCUAAUUCUGAAUCAUCACUGGGAGCAAAACACAGACUCACAGAGGAAGGGCAAGAGAAGGGUAAAGAACAAGAGAGACCACCUGAGGCAGUGAGCAAGUUUGCAAAGCGGAACAAUGAAGAAACUGUAAUGUCAGCUAGAGACAGGUACUUGGCCAGGCAGAUGGCGCGGGUUAAUGCAAAGACCUAUAUUGAGAAAGAAGAUGAUUGAUGGCUACCCCAAGAGAAAGAUUUAAGGAAGCACAGAAAACUGUAAUUCCUGGAACCUGCUGCGUAAAACCAUAAAGGAGUGUGUUACCAGUAGUUUGGAGGGCAUUUUUAAAUUUAUUUUCAAAAUUUUAAGUUAAAAGUCAGUCUUACAGCUUGGAUGUUUGGAUGUGGAUGUUUGGCUGAAUUUAUAUAUAGUGUGUACUCAUCAAUACCACAUUCUUUGUUGUAUUCAAGAACCGUUAAGAGUGUGCUAAUUCCCUGUAGGUACAUAAUGAGGAAAAUUUGCUCCACUACAACCAUUAAAAAAUAAUUUUGGCCAGAUACGGUAGCUCGUGCCUGUAAUACCAACAUUUUGGGAGGCCAAGGCAGAAGGAUAUUGAGGCUAGGCAUUCAAGACCAGCCUAGGCAGGAUAAUAAGACCUUGUCUCUAUUUAAAAAACAAAAAGCCUAGCAUGGUAGUCCAUGCCUGUAGUCCCAGCUGUUCGAGAGGCUGAGGCAAGAAGAUCACUUGAGCCUAGGAAUUUGAUGUUACAGUGAGGUAUGAUCAUGCCACUGCACUCCAACCUGGGCAACAGAAUGAGACCCUGUCUCUAAAAAAUUUUUUUUAAAUAAAUAAUUUAACUCUUCUAAUAAUGUUUUGUUGCAGGAAAUGUAUUUCAGAUAAAAUAUGGAUUUGAAAAACAGAAAAUAUACUUUAUGUUCUGAAAUUUGUAUUUAAGUAUAAAAUGUGAAUCAUCUUGUCUAAAUAGCUUACAGCAUAGUUGGCUUAAAUGAAAAUAAAAUGAUAUGCUUAUACAUUUUA